ACCCGGCGGCGGCCGCCAAGUGCCUCUGGGCGCUGCGUGCCGCGCCCGCUGCUCCGCGCGCAGCCGGCUCGGGCCGCUCCUCCUGACUGAGGCGCGGCGGCGGCGGUGGCUGUGACCGCGCGGACCGAGCCGAGACAUUCGCGCCGGGGGAUCGGGCGCCGCCGCCGCUGGGCCCCGGGCGCGUGGAUGCGGCUGGGUCGGGCGGCGCCGUACACCUGAGGCGGAGAACGGGGCGCGGCGCGGGUGACGCUGUCAGGGCCGCGGUUCCUGACGCCCAGGCGCUCGCCAGGACGAGCCAGGCAGUGAUUUGAGGCACCGGCUUCACCUUCACCCAUGGUCCGGAGAGCCUAGCGGGGCUCGCCACCGCCUCCCGGCUCCCCUUCCACGCCUCAUCCUGCCAGCCUCGCCGCCCCGCCAGCGCCGGGCAACCGCCUCGCCCGAAGCCCUCCCUCGUUACUGUCCGCAUACCCCGGCGGCGCCGCCGCGGGAAGCGGCUCCCCCUCCUCUUCCUCCGCGUCCUCUUCCCUCUUUCCCCCGCCGGGGCCGCUUGUUGCACCGCCCCGCGGCCUGCGGGAGCCGCUCGCCCCGGCCUUGUGCUCGCGUCCGCACCCCUUUCCUGUCGCCCCCCGGGGCCCGCACCACAGCCCGGCCGGCGAGACCCCGGCCAGACCCCGCUGCCCGCACAAAAUGUCGGCCCGGACGCCAUUGCCGACGGUGAACGAGCGGGACACGGAAAAUCAUACAUCUGUGGAUGGAUAUACUGAACCACACAUCCAGCCUACCAAGUCGAGUAGCAGACAGAACAUCCCCCGGUGUAGAAACUCCAUUACGUCAGCAACAGAUGAACAGCCUCACAUUGGAAAUUACCGUUUACAAAAAACAAUAGGGAAGGGAAAUUUUGCCAAAGUCAAAUUGGCAAGACACGUUCUAACUGGUAGAGAGGUUGCUGUGAAAAUAAUAGACAAAACUCAGCUAAAUCCUACCAGUCUACAAAAGUUAUUUCGAGAAGUACGAAUAAUGAAGAUACUGAAUCAUCCUAAUAUAGUAAAAUUGUUUGAAGUUAUUGAAACAGAGAAGACUCUCUAUUUAGUCAUGGAAUACGCGAGUGGGGGUGAAGUAUUUGAUUACUUAGUUGCCCAUGGAAGAAUGAAAGAGAAAGAGGCCCGUGCAAAAUUUAGGCAGAUUGUAUCUGCUGUACAGUAUUGUCAUCAAAAGUACAUUGUUCACCGUGAUCUUAAGGCUGAAAACCUUCUCCUUGAUGGUGAUAUGAAUAUUAAAAUUGCUGACUUUGGUUUUAGUAAUGAAUUUACAGUUGGGAACAAAUUGGACACAUUUUGUGGAAGCCCACCCUAUGCUGCUCCCGAGCUUUUCCAAGGAAAGAAGUAUGAUGGGCCUGAAGUGGAUGUGUGGAGUCUGGGCGUCAUUCUCUAUACAUUAGUCAGUGGCUCCUUGCCUUUCGAUGGCCAGAAUUUAAAGGAACUGCGAGAGCGAGUUUUACGAGGGAAGUACCGUAUUCCCUUCUAUAUGUCCACAGACUGUGAAAAUCUUCUGAAGAAAUUAUUAGUCCUGAAUCCAAUAAAGAGAGGCAGCUUGGAAUGCCGUAUUAAAUAAAAACAACACAAAAAUAGAGGUUGACUUUUAGUUAGAGAAGGAGGAAAACGUAGCUGCUGUCAGAAAUUGCUUUGUCGAAAACAGAAACCUUGUUUUUAGUAAGUACUCAAUAAAUAUUUCAAGGAUAAAAGAAAAUAGUGAAAAUUCUAAUCUAAUGAAUAUUUCACAGCUAUAUCUGACAUUGAUAUCUAGCAUUUAAAAAUGUAGGGCUGGGCACGGUGGCUCACGCCUGUAAUCCCAGCACUUUGGGAGGCCGAGGCGGGCAGAUCACGAGGUCAGGAGAUUGAGACCAUCCUUGCUAACAUGGUGAAACCCUGUCUGUACUAAAAAUACAAAAAAUUAGCUGGACGAGGUGGCACACACCUGUAGUCCCAGCUACUUGGGAGGCUGAGGCAGGAGAAUGGCGUGAACUUGGGAGGCGGCGCUUGCAGUGAGCCAAGAUCACGCCACUGCACUCCAGCCUGGGCGACAGAGCGAGACUCUAUCAUAAAAAAAUAAAAUAAAAUAAAAAUGUAAUAGAAACCUCUCAACUUUAGUAAAGAAAAUUUACAAAUAUUUAAGUACAACAUACUGGAAACAGGCAUUUCAUUUCUUAGCACACUGUUGUGUUGCCUACAUAUGUUCUGUAUGUGAGGUUAUUUAUAAUAAUAGACACUAUUAUAAAUGGACUAAGUAUGUUACAGCCAAGCAAGUUCACAUAACCAAAAUGUCUACUAUUUUUUUUCUUCUGGCACUGCAAUUAGAAUAAUUUAUUUCUUAAGUAUUUUGCCCAUCUGUUUUUAAGAAUGAUAUUUUAGCCUUUACUAAGAUAAUUUCAGAGAUUCAGCAUGCAUUAUUCACUAGUACUUUCUGUCUUCUUUUAUUUACCUUAAUAGAAAGGGUAGAGAAUUCAGAGAAUUAACCUCAUAUAAACUGUACUUUUUUAGUGUAGCAAUGGGGCUUUCUGGCAUGGACUUCAUGCUGCUUAGGAGGCAGCCUUAUAGUGAGCCAUCCCUGUGUACAGAGCUCUCAGGUUAGUGUGGGCUUUGUAAUUUUAUUUCCACAAAUAUUUUUCAGUAGAGGAUACAGCAUGUUUUGAUGGAAGUUAAGGGAUGGCGACUUCCAUUGGGAAAUUAUUUUAAAUGCUUUGUGUCAGUUAGUCAAUUAUCAUGAUUUUUUUACCGAAUUAUUUGUUUAAAUGUGAUUAGUUAUAGCUUAUGAGUUUUGUGGGCUUUUCCCUCCUUAUGGGGUUAAAAAAAAUGAGUUAAUGCUUUAAUAGAGAACAUGUACUAUAUAAUGCCCACUUUUAUAUCACUUAUUUUGAAAGCUUUCCAUCAUUAUUCAUAGAAAAAUUAGGUGAAAUAUUUAAAAAGCUAAAAUUUUUGACUCUCAUAUCAGUUCUAAAAUAAUGAACUUUAGAGAACAUGUUUUGUAAUCCUGUUUUGUGACUAACUUUUAUCAUAAGAACCCCACUUGACCUGAGUGACACAAUAAAAUGCUCAAAGUUGAAGCAGCAGCUUAGCUAAUGAGCAGAGCAAAAAGAACAUACAAAAAUUAUUUUGGGGGGAUAGAUAUUACAGAUCUCUAUGGACAGUAGGUAAGAUGUGCUUAUGUCUUAAAGAUGAUUAAUUUAUAGUAGCCAAACACUUUAGUCUUUUAUCAUUAUUAUUAACAUGUUGAGGAUUAAAAUAUUAGAGUGCUUUGAGUUGAAUUUAAAAGCCAAAUUUUUAUUACUAAAAUAUUUGAUCAUCAGAAGCUCAUUCUAAUAUAUUUCAGUAUAGUCUGCAACUUUCUGUUCCAGCUUACCAAAACAAAGUUUUUCAGCUAUGAAACCACGAGUCCCCACUGGAAAUAUUAUAUUAUAGAUAUUACUAUACAAAGGCUGAUUUGCUUCACAGUUCCCAGAAAUGACUUUCCAGGGAAACUUGACACCAUUUUUUAAAAAAGAAAUAUUUCUUAUACCAUACCUUAAGAAACUCUCCUAGAAAUAUUGGUGACUUCAAAAAUUGUUAGUCUUCACUUUUAUUUUUCAUACCAAUUUUAUUAGCUUUACAGUAAAAAACCUGUAAACUUUUUUAAAGCUAUUUUCAAAAUACUCAUCUUUAUUAUGUAAAUAUAACAUUUUAUGUGUUAGUAAUGUUUUAUAUUAUGUUCCAUUCUUUUUUUUAACCUUAGAAGCUUUUGAUAUGCACUUCUUGCUUUGUCAUAAGAAUGCACUCCUUCCUUUUUAAUAGCUAUGUUAUUCUCCUUGGGUUACGUAACGUAAUUUAUUUAACUAUUCCCUGCUUAUUGCACAUCUGAGUUGUUUCCAUUGUUUUUGAUAAAAAACAAUGUGGUAUACUUUUUUCCCCUUUGGGAUAUAUGUUUAGAUAAAUUCUUCAGAGUGGAAUUACUGGGUCAAAGGGUGUAAGUGAUCGGAUAGCUCUUUUAUCAUUGCCAAAAGAUAUGUGUGACCCAAGGCUUUUGAAUGUACCUAUUCUCCAUACCCUGAUUCAAUAAUGGAUACAAAUUCUAGUAUUUGAUGCCUCGCUUUAAUUUGUAUUUCUUUUAUUAGCAAUAAAAUGGAAUAUUUUUAAUGAAUAGUUUGUGCUUCUUCAUGUAUAAGCUCUCAGUGUCUUUUAACUACUUGUCUUAAGGAGUCUGGUUAAUAAGCCUCGUAGAUUUGUACCAACUUUGUAUAUUUUAAUAUAAAAUAUUUUUCUGGUAAUUUCCACAUUUAAAAAAAAUGGAACAUCAUGAAUGUUUUUUCAGUGUUACUUUAGUGUCAUGAAUUAUUGAUUAGAGUAUCCUCUAGUCUUUCUUCACUAUAUAUUUUGCUAAUAUUGAAAUUUGAUUUAGAGAAUUUUACAUGGUUGCAUAUUGUUUCAAACUUAUUUAACUUACCUUUCUGUUGCUACCAGACAUAACUGUGUAUUUUAUUAAAGUGUUUCUUAAAGACUCAUAAGUUAAAUGCCUUAUUUAUCAUCUGUGAAAAUAAAAAUUAUUGAAAUUAGUUUCACAUUCUACUAGGCCUAUAGUUUGUUUCUAGACAUAAGCAAACAGUUAUAUAAUUUUUUCAGGUUAUAUAUGUGAAUGCUGUCAGCUCUUUCUAAUUGUACUAGUCUGGAACUUCCAUGUGUUAUACUGUCCUCUCAUAAUGAGGGCAUUAUGAUUUUAAACGGAUUUGUGCUUUAUGUUGUACACUAGGGUUUUUUUUAACCCAUUUAUUGGAAUAUUAGUAUGUCUAGAUUUUUUUAUUAGAAAGAAACUGAAAAACUUUUCUGCUUUCCCUGUUUUGUAUGUGUUCAUUCAUUUUUCCAGUGUUUAACCAAGAUGGACUAUAUUACCUUUCAAAACAAUGCAAAAUUUGAGCCUGAAGCAAAGCUCCUCUUAUUGCCCUCUCUUUGUCGUCAUUGGUCCUCCCAUAAAAGUGUUUAUUUUGACUUUUGAUACUUAAUUUUUCAGGUGUUACUAAAAUAAUCUUUACAGUCUUGUUUAUGUCUGCCAAAUGACAGUAAAGCAAAAAAAUCAAUUAAUUCAUAAUUUUUUAAUGAAAGAUUUCUGUGUACAAAUUCAGAAGCAUAUAGUAUAUUUUACAAAGGUUGAAAUCAUUUAAGUAAAAUUAUUUGUCUGGCCGUUCUAAAUUCCAUAUUUUUAAAAUGUGCACCUCAGGCCAGGCUUGAUGGCUCAUGACUGUAAUCCAAAUACUUUGGGAGGCCAAGGCGGGCAGAUCACCUAAGUCCAGGAGAUCGAGACCAGCCUGGGCAACAUGGAAAAACCCUGUCUCUACAUUAGCUGGGCGUGGUGUCACACAUCCUGUAGUCCUAGCUACUCGGGAGGCUGAAGCACGAGGAUUGCUUGAGCCCAGGAGGUUGAGGAUGCUGUAAGCCAUGAUUGCGCCACUGGACUGCAGCCGGGAUGACAGAACAAGACCCUGUCUCCAAAUAAGAUAAAAUAAAAUAAAUGUGCAUCUAAGUAUAGAGUGUAUAUUUCCCA